AUACAAAGGAACUCCAUCAUACCGGAUGCCACCGUUUAAGGAUCCUUUGAAACUUCUUAAGAAUUCAACGAGAUUUUUAACCUGAAACUGAAGAAUCUGGUACUGUAAGUGUAAAGAAGCUUAUUUUGGAAGCCAAUUUCGUAUGCGAUGUUUGGUUUUCAGAGAAGGGGAUUGGGCACCCCACGACUACAGCUCUGGCUUCUCCUCCUCGAAUUCUGGGAGGUGGGGAGCGGCCAGCUCCACUACUCCGUCUCGGAGGAGGCCAAACACGGCACCUUCGUGGGCCGCAUCGCGCAGGACCUGGGGCUGGAGCUGGCGGAGCUGGUGCAGCGCCUGUUCCGGGUGGCGUCCAAAACACAUGGGGACCUUCUGGAGGUAAAUCUGCAGAAUGGCAUUUUGUUUGUGAAUUCUCGGAUCGACCGCGAGGAGCUGUGCGGGCAGAGCGCGGAGUGCAGCAUCCACCUGGAGGUGAUCGUGGACAGGCCGCUGCAGGUUUUCCAUGUGAACGUGGAGGUGAAGGACAUUAACGACAACCCGCCGGUGUUCUCGCUCAGAGAACAAAAGCUGCUGAUUGCGGAAUCUAAGCAAUCGGACUCGCGUUUUCCACUAGAGGGAGCUUCUGAUGCUGACAUUGAAGAGAAUGCUCUAUUGACCUACAGGCUAAGUAAAAAUGAGUAUUUUUCUUUAGAUUCACCAACAAAUGGUAAGCAGAUUAAAAGACUGUCACUUAUUUUAAAGAAGUCUCUGGAUAGAGAGAAAACUCCGGAACUUAAUUUGCUGCUAACAGCUACAGACGGGGGAAAACCAGAGCUUACUGGCACCGUUCGGCUGUUAGUCCAAGUCUUGGAUGUCAACGACAAUGAUCCAGAGUUUGAUAAAUCAGAAUAUAAGGUGAGCCUUAUGGAAAAUGCUGCUAAAGAAACUCUUGUGCUCAAACUAAACGCCACAGACCGAGACGAAGGAGUCAAUGGAGAGGUAACAUACUCCUUAAUGUCAAUUAAGCCCAAUGGAAGACACUUAUUUACACUAGAUCAAAAUAAUGGAGAAGUGAGGGUCAAUGGAACUUUAGAUUAUGAAGAAAACAAGUUUUAUAAAAUUGAAGUACAGGCUACAGAUAAGGGGACUCCCCCAAUGGCAGGUCACUGUACAGUCUGGGUGGAAAUCUUGGACACCAACGAUAACUCUCCUGAAGUCGCCGUGACUUCCUUGUCCCUCCCAGUACGAGAGGACGCUCAGCCCAGCACGGUCAUUGCCCUGAUCAGCGUGUCUGACCGUGACUCAGGUGUCAACGGACAGGUGACCUGCUCGCUGACGCCCCACGUUCCCUUCAAGCUGGUGUCCACCUUCAAGAAUUACUACUCGUUGGUGCUGGACAGCGCCCUGGACCGCGAGAACGUGUGGGCCUAUGAACUGGUGGUGACUGCGCGGGAUGGGGGUUCGCCUUCUCUGUGGGCCACGGCCAGGGUAUCCGUGGAGGUGGCCGACGUGAACGACAAUGCGCCUGCGUUCGCACAGCCCGAGUACACCGUGUUCGUGAAGGAGAACAACCCACCAGGCUGCCACAUCUUCACAGUGUCGGCGCGGGACGCGGACGCGCAGGAGAACGCGCUGGUGUCCUACUCGCUGGUGGAGCGGCGGUUGGGCGACCGCGCGCUGUCGAGCUACGUGUCGGUGCACGCGGAGAGCGGCAAGGUGUACGCGCUGCAGCCGUUGGACCACGAGGAGCUGGAGCUGCUACAGUUCCAGGUGAGCGCGCGCGAUGCGGGCGUGCCGCCUCUGAGCAGCAACGUGACGCUGCAGGUGUUCGUGCUGGACGAGAACGACAACGCGCCGGCACUGCUGGCGACUCAGGCUGGCAGCGCGGGAGGCGCAGUUAACAAGCUAGUACCGCGGUCGGUGGGUGCGGGCCACGUGGUGGCGAAGGUGCGCGCAGUGGAUGCGGACUCAGGCUACAACGCGUGGCUUUCAUAUGAAUUGCAGCCGGCGGCGGGCGGCUCGCGCAUCCCGUUCCGCGUGGGGCUGUACACGGGCGAGAUAAGCACAACGCGUGCCCUGGACGAGGCAGACUCGCCGCGCCACCGACUUCUAGUACUGGUGAAGGAUCACGGUGAGCCGGCGCUGACGGCCACGGCCACCGUGCUGGUGUCGUUGGUGGAGAGCGGACAGGCGCCAAAGGCCUCUUCCCGGACUUUGGCGGGCGCCGCGAGCCCAGAGGCUGCGCUGGUGGAUGUCAACGUGUACCUGAUCAUCGCCAUCUGCGUGGUGUCCAGCCUCCUGGUACUCACGCUGCUGCUGUAUACGGCGCUGUGGUGGUCGGCAACGCCCACUGAGGGCGCGUGCGCGCCGGGGAAGCCCACGCUGGUGUGCUCCCGCGCGGUGGGGAGCUGGUCAUACUCGCAGCAGAGGCGGCAGAGGGUGUGCUCUGAGGAGGGCCCACCUAAGACGGACCUCAUGGCCUUCAGCCCCAGUCUUCCUCUAGGUCUGAAUAAAGAGGAGGAAGGGGAAAGACAGGAGCCAGGGUCAAAUCACCCCGGACAGCCACGACAGCCCAACCCUGACUGGCGUUACUCUGCCUCCCUGAGAGCAGGCAUGCACAGCUCUGUGCACCUAGAGGAGGCUGGCAUUCUACGGGCUGGUCCAGGAGGGCCUGAUCAGCAGUGGCCAACAGUAUCCAGUGCAACACCAGAACCAGAGGCAGGAGAAGUGUCCCCUCCAGUCGGUGCGGGUGUCAACAGCAACAGCUGGACCUUUAAAUACGGACCAGGCAACCCCAAACAAUCCGGUCCCGGUGAGUUGCCCGACAAAUUCAUUAUCCCAGGAUCUCCUGCAAUCAUCUCCAUCCGGCAGGAGCCUACUAACAGCCAAAUUGACAAAAGUGACUUCAUAACCUUCGGCAAAAAGGAGGAGACCAAGAAAAAGAAGAAAAAGAAGAAGGGUAACAAGACCCAGGAGAAAAAAGAGAAAGGGAACAGCACGACUGACAACAGUGACCAGUGAGGUCCUCAAAUGGAAACAAGCCACUUAGCCAGUUUUUGUAAUAAUGGCAAAUCUCUCCCAUGUAGCAAUUCCCUGCUCCUUUUUCCUAUCUACAUGAGCCCUCUUAGAGACCUCAGAAAUCUGCAGAAAGUUCCCUGUGUCUGUCUAGAACGCAUUUAACAGGUUUUGUCGUAAAAGCUUUACUAAGUCUGGUGUUAACUCUUUCUCUCCACUCUGGCUUGUUUUCAGAACCUAAAAAGCAGACCCAAGUUUCCUUUCUCCUCCGCCGCAAAGGAGAGGCUUCCCAGCCCCGCCAGUGAGAGGUUGGACUCUCUGCCCUGUGCUCCGGGGAUCCUGUCUUGAUGACACUUGCAGGGCAGGCUGAAAAGUUUUGAGAUUGAGCAGCUUGGGAGUUUGUGGCCACUGGGUAUGUGUGGCUACCGCGGGUAUGCGAGUGCCAGAUAUUGGCUGAGACGAGCCAGCUUAGACUAAUUGGUACAAGGAAGGCAAGAAAACAAAGACAAAUAAACAGCGGAAGUUAUCAGUAUGGAGGGGAAGUGUAAACUUAAAGGGACCAGACUUUCUAAAUCUUACAACUCAAGAGGUGGCAGCCACCCUCUAGGAGACAAAACUACCCCCACUGACAAGGCUUUAGGAGACCCUAAAGUCUGUUGGCUGUGACGUCAUUAUACCUAAAAUCUGCAUCAUACCUGCAAGCCAACAGUUCAGUGUUUUAACAGAGAACCACCCUGGGAAACAGAAGCAGAUCUGAUGUGUUUCCUAUACAUGUCCUGUGCUCACUUUAUUAAAAAUUCUUUUGCACACAAUGUUUAUGAAAAGGCCAGAUCCUUUUCCAAUACUUAUGCAAAAGCAAAAGAAAACCCCGACACCUCACCUUUCGCUGUUUGUUGUUUCAUAGAUUUAUUUAAAAAAAGAGAAAGUCUAUAGCUAUAAAUCUUUAAAGAGAAAUAUGAAUACAAUUCCCCUAAACUCUCCUCAAAAGAGAAUUCAGUCUACAGCCAUUUAAAUGAUCAUUGCUGCUACAGAAGUGCUUUAAGAGAAUUGCCUGAAACAUCUGUAUUAUAUCGGCCACCUGCCAAUCACAGCUUUACUCUUUCAGGUCACUCUGGGGCUGCCUCUUGCAUGUAUUACUAAAUAAAAUGAUCUCUCUUUCUCUCUCUCUCUCUCUUUUCUAAGAAACAAUUAUGUGCACUUUGAUACACAACCUUCUCUAACCAACUAUAUAUCAAGACCCAAAAAUUGAAGAAAAAUAUUGUUUUCUCAUACAGUGAGCAGAUUUUUCAAUCUACUAAUUCUGUGACUUGUCUUGGUGUGCUAGCCUACACCUUCUCUUUGGUUUAGUUUUCCUUUUCUAUAACACUCUGAAUUGCUAAUCUUACUAACACCUAUGAUGUUACCUGAAAUCAAUCUCCCAUAUGUAUGCUGUAUGCUAUGCUAAGACUCCUGAAAUAUACUUACUCUGUGCUUGUGUAUGUGAAUGUUAAUGCAACUAUUACCUAGAGUGAACUUUAAGCUUUAUUGUUGAAUGUAAUUCCAUUAUAUUUCCUUUUGUACACCUGUGAAAAAGUGGAGUAGUGUUUUUUUAACCAUUGUUAAUCAGCUUUUGUGUAUGAAAGACACAGUAAAAUUUCUUUCUUAAAUCAAGAUACUGGUGAUUCAAGGAAUUUUAUUUAUGGUCCAGCCAAGAGCCAUCUCGUGCCAAGACUUCUGCUGGCAAGGGAAUGGAUAAAGCUGUUUUGUUCUAGUAACAAUUUUGGAAUGAAUACUGACAAUAUUCCAUGAGGGUGUGCAAGCACAAAUUUUACCAAUCUGACCUCUUUGAAGUUGCAGAAUGCUUUGAAAUUCUAAUGGUAUCUGAAAUAUCAGCUCAUAGAAAGUAACAAAAUUUGCUGUCACCUUAAAUAAGACAUUUUAAUUUUGUUAUAAUGUACAAUUUAGAAGUUUGAUUAAUUAUAUUAUCUAUUUAGGCAUUAAUAUAAAAGAGGUAGGAGUCUGUUAUUUAAAAAAAGCAUUAAAUUUAAAAAAAAACUGUCUUGUCUACUUUUAGCUUCAUUCUCCCAUAUUUUGAAGGGUGUGUAACUUCAGCUCUGCAGGAUUGCAUGGGGUAAAACUUGUUACCAACACAUGUGAACCAUUGCUACAUUGUAGGUUGUGAUCAUUUUGCCCCACUGAAGCCCAUGUAUCUGACCUUACGUGCCUUUUGAACUAGGAGAAUCGGGCUAAUUUAUUAAUGAUGAUAAUUAUAAUGUAUCUGUACAGCACUUUUUACAUUUGCGAAGUGCUUUCCAAUCCAUGUUAGUUACUAGUUAUUACAGCUGUAAGGAUAAAACACGUCAUGUGGAUUCAUUUUGAAUUGGUGCUAUUGGUAUUUCCUCUGUUAUUGCUAAUAAAUGAAAAUGGUGGUAUGAAA